GCACGCACGCGCACUGCGCCCAGCAUGAGGGUCGCGGCUCUGAUCAGUGGUGGGAAGGACAGCUGCUAUAAUAUGAUGCAGUGCAUUGCUGCUGGGCAUCAGAUCGUUGCUUUAGCAAAUCUAAGACCAGCUGAAAACCAAGUGGGGUCUGAUGAACUGGAUAGCUACAUGUAUCAGACAGUGGGGCACCAUGCCAUUGACUUGUAUGCAGAAGCAAUGGCUCUUCCCCUCUAUCGCCGAACCAUAAGAGGAAGGAGCUUGGAUACAAGACAAGUGUACACCAAAUGUGAAGGUGAUGAGGUUGAAGAUCUCUAUGAGCUUUUGAAACUUGUUAAGGAAAAAGAAGAAGUAGAGGGGAUAUCAGUAGGUGCUAUACUUUCUGACUAUCAGCGUAUUCGAGUGGAAAAUGUGUGUAAAAGGCUUAAUCUCCAGCCUUUAGCUUAUCUUUGGCAGAGAAACCAGGAAGAUUUGCUCAGAGAGAUGAUAUCAUCUAACAUUCAAGCAAUGAUCAUCAAAGUAGCAGCUUUGGGUUUAGAUCCUGAUAAGCAUCUUGGGAAAACCCUGGAUCAAAUGGAGCCUUAUCUCAUAGAGCUUUCUAAGAAGUAUGGAGUACAUGUUUGUGGAGAAGGUGGAGAGUAUGAAACUUUCACUUUGGAUUGCCCUCUAUUUAAGAAGAAAAUAAUUGUGGAUUCAUCAGAAGUAGUCAUACAUUCAGCUGAUGCAUUUGCACCUGUGGCUUAUCUACGCUUUUUAGAAUUGCACUUGGAGGACAAGGGCAGAACAGCAUAAAAUAAGCAGAAUUACAAGUUUGAUUAUCAAACUCUGUAAGUAUAUCACGUUCGUUUGUUAUUUGUAUUCAGAGAAUGUGAGGGUGAGACUAUGUAAUUUAGCUGCAGCUUGCUGAGUUUUGUUUUUUUUUUUUUACCAUCCAAAUAGCUUCAUAGAGAUGAGCUUUGAAGAAUGGCUUAAACAUACUGUUUUUUUAUUUCUUCUCAGGUUAGUGUCACUUCAAAAAUAAAAAUAAAAAUAGGCACUCUUACUGGAACAUCAGGAGUAAUGCUGGGUAUAAACAGGAUUAGAAUAUACUUAACUGUGGUAAUCCUUCCCGACACACAUAGAGAUGAAUUGAUAACUGGAUUUGGCAUUUCAAAUAUUUUUUACCAAGGCAAAGGCUUUAGGGUGUUUUCUCGGAAUUAGAGAGUUUAGAGAUGAAAAAGGUACCAUUUAUUAUUUUCUCUUUCUGUCAGCUUAGGACUUCUCUUUGCAAUCAUGUUUAUAAUACUGGGCCUGUCUGUUCUUAAAUGUUUCACCUGUUGAAGGAUGUUCCAUCAGAGGGUGUGCUAAAAUCUUAGAUUGUAUGUGCCAGAGGUUUUGACUGAAUAAUAUUCUGAUAAAAUCAAGGAAGGUAAUGUAUUGGAAAGGAACUUGGGCUUACAAUCAGCAGUAGUGAGUUCUAGUCAGGAAUCUGUAAUAUAAUCUGUACAUGAUCUUGAGCAAAUCACUUAGUGUCUCUCAAUUUUCUGUUUCCUCAUGUGAGAUGUGAAAGGUUUUGGCUAGCCUAUAUUAUUCAGUUUGUUAGAUAAUCAGAUAAAUAUAUCAUUUAAUCAAAUUAACCACAUCAGUGUAUCAGUUCAGCCAAAAUAUUUGUCAUUUAUAUAAGAAAGACUAUAAGAAAUCAGAAAACUAGAUUUUUAUUUUCUUAACAAUAGUACUACUUUGCCAAGUAAUGGCAACUUAAAAGAGCUUUCUCUCAAACCUGGCAGUAUUACACCAUUUUUGCUACAAUAUUAUUUUCAGGAAUAUAAUCACGGCUUACCUAUUACCAGGGCCUUAGAGUAUAAAUGAAAAAAAAAUGAUUAGCUUUUGCAAUCCUACUUUAUCCUGGGACUCAAUAAAGAAAAUUAGUAUCCUUCUUUAAAAAAAAAGGGGAAAAAAGAUGACUAUAUUCCCAUUCCUCCAAAAUAUAGAAUAUCAAAUGAAGAGUAAAUAGACACUAACCUCUCCUCCCCCUUUUUUUUUUUUAACUCCAGAGCUAACUGAUCUGAAUAAUUUUCUCUUCACCAAAACUGGUAGAAUAUUUUACUUUAUCAUCAGGUUAUUUUUGAUUGCAAAGCUGUAACGUCACAGUAUACUUAUACUGAAAAAUGCAUAGGAUUUGGAAUCAGGAGAUCUAGCUUCAAGAAUCUGUUCUAUUACCUCAUAUAUAUAUAAUUUGAGUAAUUUCUUUAAAGGUUUAAGGAAACCUUUGAAUCUUGGUUUCCUAAUUACUAACAAGGCAGUAGCAGUAAUAUUUGUCAUUGGAACGUCUAUUGGUAAGAAAUUAAAUAAUGAAUGUGAAUCAUAAAGACUAGUAUGCCUUCUUAUUAGCGCUAUUAUAAAAAUAUUUUAAAAUAUUUUAUAUUUAAUAAAUUGUAUUACUUUCAUCUGACUACAUAUAGAUAACAUCGCACCUUUAUAGACAGUAUUAUUAAGUUCAAAUAUUAAAGAUGGAAGGAAGGAAGAGGAAUGGAACUAAUAUUUCUGGAGCACCCUGCCACAGCAUCAUGAUGGAAAAGUCAGGGAGUGCUUUAUUUUCUAACUCCAAUGUAAUGUACUUUCUAACUGCUGUGUAAGAGACAAUGCACCACCACAUUGUCACCUGUGUAAGAGAAGGAAACUCAACCCUUUGGGGUUCUUAAAUUGUAGAACAAAGAAGACUUGCCCCAAUAUGGAGAAACUCUAGUUUUUCUUGACCACUUCCUUUCUGCACCAUUUCUCCAAAUUUUAUUUUUUAAUAUAGAAACCAUUAUAAGUAUAUAGCUUACAAAUCUAAUCAAUAUGUUUCCACACAAAUCUGCAAACUGAUUUGUAUAUAAGAAGACCCUAUUCAAGUUUGAAUUCAGGUGGUUAUUUAGCUGAAAUGCCAUGAGAAAAAAAAAAAAGAAAAAUCGUCUUCAUUGUGAAUUUGAGAUAAUUACUUUCAAAAAUCACUGCAGCCCCAAUCCAAGAAGGGACCACAGGGUUUAAUUGUGGGUGUGCUAUUUACAGAUUAAUUAGGACAUUUAACUUCAUUUUUUAUACCACAGAAUUAAUCCCAUAAAAAUUAGUGAUCUCGAAGGAGUCAGUUGUCAAACUCUGACAGGAUCUCUUUGCCAUAAUCUAUUAAAAUGCUGCUUUUAUCUUGUCUUGCCUGUGUCAUAUUUUAUGGAUUUUUUCAUAAACACUGCCUAUACUUCAUAAAUGUCUCAAUUUUCUAGUCUAUUAACAUUACUUCAAAAGCAAUUGAUAAAAGAGUAGGGCAUGCAUGAAAUAAUACACCAAUAAUGUGAAGUGCUGGAGGCAAGAACAGUGGGUAGGAUCUGCACAGCUUGUGAGCUGAAACAAUGAAAGGAUGUUUUAUCUACUACAAUAAAGAAACAAAUGAUCAUUUUUGAUAGUAGAAAAGAGAUUGCUAGUAAUUGGGCAGAUGAAAAAUGGGUUAUACAGAAAAUACAGCAUAGUUUGAAAAUGAUAACUGAAAUGAGAAAAUAAAUGUCCCCAAGUAUAUAUUUACAUUAGUGGAAACCUUUUCCCUUUUGUUACCAAAGAUUUGGUAUUCAGUUUGAUUUGUCUUAGUUCUAGAUAUGAUGGUUUUAUUCUAUAUAUAAAUAUUUCCUUUGUAUGCAUAUAUUUUUACCAAACCUAUAUAUGUAUUUUAUGUAUUGACUACAAUAAAUGUUGGAAUUUGGUUUUUAAAUCUUUUUAAUUAUUAUUAUUAUUAUUUUGAGAUGGAGUCUCACUCUGCCGCCCAGGCUCGAGUGCAGUGGCACUAUCUUAGCUCACUGCAACCUCCGCCUCCCAGGUUCAAGCAGUUAUCCUGCCUCAGCCUCCCAAGUGGCUGGGAUUACAGGCACAUGCCACCACACCCAGCUAAUUUUUUAUAUUUUUGGUAGAGAUGGGGUUUUACCAUGUUAGCCAGGCCGGUCUCAAACUCCUGACCUCAAGUGAUUCACCCACCUUGGCCUCCGAAAGUGCUGGGAUUACAGAGGCAUGAGCCACCACGCCCGGCCUAAUUUUUUUAUUCUAGUUUUUGAAGUUAUUUUAAUUUUUCUUUUAAUGUAUAGAUGAUAUGUCUAUAGCAUCCUCUUUAGAUUUCUUAAGCCCUAAUAUAAGACCUAAUAUAAUUAAAUAAGAAUCUUAAUUUGGAUUUGUACCACAAAUUUAAUUGAAUAAACUGACUUUUCAAAAACUUAUUUGGUAAUUAUGUAUUUAAAUCAACUAAAUGAAAAACAAAGAGGAGAAAAGUCACUGAGCAAGAUGCAGAAUUCCUAAUUUUUCUUUCAUGUUAUUCUUCGUAUUUUACCACCUGACUUAGCUAAAUAAAGCCAGAUAUUGUCUGAGCUUUCAUUCUUAAGGCAUCAUGUUAUAAACAGAGUGACCUUAGAGCUCAGUAUGUCUGCACAGUCCUGGUGUUUUCCUGUAAUUAUCAAUAGCUCCUCCUUUCACUUUCAUAAGUGUCCUGGCUUGGAUGACAAAGUCAUGGUUACCUAUUAAAAUAUGUGAUCAAGUAAAUAUUGGAAGAAAUGUUUGAGUAAUACAUACGGUUUUAAAUUUCUCAAAACCUACAUAGUACUAUGUAAAAUAAUUAGUGUGAUUUAGUGUUAAGGUCUUUGGUUCUUGAUUCAUAUAAUUCCUUUUUUAACUUGGAAAUGAGACCAUUUUCUUGUUGCUCAGAUCAAGAAAUAAUCUCAGAUAACUCAAGUGUGAUCAUUCAAUUCUAAUACUUGAAAAGAAGAUGAUUUUUCUCAUGCCUUGAUAGAUGGUGAUAGAAUACAUUGCUGAAUUGUCCUAGUGGCACUCUAUAAAACAGGUAAUGUAGUGGGGUGAAGUACAGGACUCAUCAUAAUGAUGAUGCCAUGUGUGCCUGUAAGCUUACAGGGGCACAGAAGAUCAUGACCAAGGGGGAUUCUUUAGUUCUCAAAUGUUGCAAAGAAUAUUUGAAACUCCCUGUCCUUGGUACAUAACUUAUGGAAACAGUCAACAAAAUUAUGUGGAAAAUAUCCAGACUUACCAUAUGGGGUGAAAGAUAAUACCCAACGUAAUAGUUUAUUAACUUGACUUAAUUCCCACUUCUCUCCCAUUUGUCUUUUCCCACGUCAGGAAACAGCAUAAAUACUCACCCAGUUGCUCAAGCCAAAAACAUAGGCAUUUUUCAUGUUCUCUUUUGUCCAUUACAUCCGUAAACAAAUGCUGCCACUUUAGUCCCGGAACGAUUCAGAAUCUACCUGCUGCUUUUCAUCUCCGUUCUUACAAUCAUAACCCGAGCUACCUUCAUUCUUCUCUACGGUUUUACAAUUGCCAUGUUACCUGCUCUGCCUGCUUCUACUCUGGCUGCCUCCUCCAUGAUUUAUUCUCAAUGUAGUACUCAAAAUGAUCUUUUAAGAAUGUAAGUCUGAUUACACAAUUCAAUAGCUUCCGUUACAUUUAAAACAAAACCCAAGCUUCUCACUGUGGCCUAUGAGUACUACAUGAUUAUACCCUUGUCUGCCCCAUCUCCUACCAUUUUUUCAUUUUUCACUGUGCUCCAUCUUCCAUUUUUGUUCAUUCAGCAUGCCAAGCUUGUUCUCAUUUGCUGUUGCCCCUGCAUGGGUGGCCUAAAACAAAUGAUUUUCUUCCCAAGUGUUUGUGAAAUCCAUUCACUUCUCACCACUUCUGUGCUCACAGUCCUAGUACAAGCGCCCAUCGUCACUCAUCCAAACUGCCCUAGCAACUUCCUCACUGGUCUCCGCGUGUUAAAUCGGCUAUCCAGCCAGGGUGAUAUUUUGAUAAGUGCAUGUUUGAUUGUGUUGAGCCCUAGAACUAUAUUCUAGGAGCUGAACAUGCAGCCCUGGCCUGAUAGAGUUUAUAUUUUAUUGGAGAAGCAGAUACCAAGCACGCACAAAAAAGAAUACUUUCAGAUUCUGCUAAAUACUAUGAAGAAAAUAAGUCGAGACUUAGUGAUAGAGAAUAAUUGAGGCGAGAUCCAUUUUUAGAUUAGGGAGUCAGGGAAGUCUUUCCCUAAGGUGUAUCUAUGUGAACAGCUGGGGAGAGGCAGGAAGGAGUUAGGAAUGGGGAAACAUAGUGAGUGAGAAAGAACAUGUUAGAGAUGGGGCGCGCUCUCCCAGCAGCCCGCGCUACCUGACCCCGCGCCGCCCAGCGCCCCGCGGACUCAGCGGAGGGUGGUGCCGCCGUUGGCUCCUGCCUCCCCGGCUCCGCGCUGCCGCCACCGCGGCCCAUGGGCAGAGUCGGCGGGCGGGCCGGCAUUAAACCGAAGAAAAGAUGUCCCUGUACGAUCAGAGGAAACCAGUGACUCAAAAACAGAAGGCUGGUCCAAAAACUUCAAACUUCUACAGUCUCAGCUUCAGGUGAAGAAGGCAGCUCUCACUCAGGCAAAGAGCCAAAGGACGAAACAAGGUACAGUUCUUGCCCCAGUCAUUGACCUACAACGAGGUGGCUCCUCAGAUGACCGGGCAAAUUGUGGACACACCACCGCAUGUGCCAGCUGGGCUGAAGGAUCCUGUUCCCAGUGGGUUUUCUGCAGGGGAAGUUCUGAUUCCCUUAGCUGACGAAUAUGAUCCUAUGUUUCCUAACGAUUGUAAGAAAGUAGUGAAACGCCAGAGAGGAAGGACAAAGACAGCGGGAGCUGGAAAGACAGAAGAAAUAGAAGAAAGAGAAGAAAGGCAUAAAUACAGACAUGAUGCACGUGAGUUUUCAAGGAGUUCAGAUCCGGAUUCUGAUGAAGAUGAAGAUUAGGAGCGAGAGAAGAGGAAAACAAGUAUGGGCGGAGCUGCCAUUGCCUCACCCACUUCUCUGGCAGUAAAAGACAGUUACCCCGAGAUUUUCCUUAUGAAGAGGACUCAAGACCUCGAUCACAGUCUUCCAAAACUGCCAUUCCUCCCCCAGUGUACGAGGAACAAGACAGACCGAGAUCUCCAACCCGGCCCAGCGCAACUCCUUCCUCGCUAACUUGGGGGGCACGGUGGCGCACAAGAUCAUACAGAAGUACGGCUUCCGGGAGGGCCAGGGUCUGGGGAAGCAUGAGCAGGGGCUGAGCACCGCCUUUUCGGUGGAGAAGACCAGCAAGCUUGGUGGCAAGAUCAUCGUGGGUGACGCCACGGAGAAAGAUGCAUCCAAGAAGUCAGAUUCAAAUCCACUGACUGAAAUACUUAAGUGUCUUAAUAAAGUGGUCCUACUAAGGAACAUGGUUGGUGCGGGAAAGGUGGAUGAAGACUUGGAAGUUAAAACCAAGGAAGAACGUGAAAAAUAUCUCAAAGUUGGGGAAAGUGUGUUGUUUGAAAUUCUGGUGCCCCUGAUGAUGAAGCAGUACGGAUAUUUUUAGAAUUUGAGAGAGUUAAAUCAGCAAUUCAAGCGGUUAUUGACUCGAAUGGGAGGUAUUUUGGUGGACAGGUGGCAAAUGCAUGUUUCUACAAUUUGGAAAAAUUCAGUAUCUUGGAUUUGGCAGAACAAGUUUGAUUUUAAGAACUAGAGCACAAGUCAUCUCCGGUGAUCCUUAAAUGAACUGCAGGCCGAGAAAAGAAGGAAAAAGGUCACAGCCUCCAUGACUGUUGCAUACUGAGACUCUUGGAGGGACUUGUAAGAUAUAUGUUGGUUGAUCCCUUUUUUAUUUUGUGGCUUUUUAAUAUAGUAUAAAAAUCCGUUUACAAAAAAAACAAAAAGAAAAUGUUAGAGAUAAGAUUGGAGAGAUGGGAGGCAAUAAUAAGAUAAAGAGCAGUGGAUUUGGCACAUAAUCUGGAGGUAGAAUUAACAGAGGUUGCUGAUGAUUGGUGAUGGAAGGGUAGAAAUUAAGGAUGAAACCUAGGUUUUUGCCUUGGCCACCAAAUAAAUGGUAGUCUUAUAAAUUGAGAUGGAGAAGUGUAGGGAAGGAGAGGGUUUGUUAGUGGAGAGAAAGUUUUUUUGACAGGGGUGGCUGGAGCAGGUUAAAUUGACUGUAUCUAGUAGACCACUAAGUGGCUGUAUCAAGCAGGUAGAUGAUUGUGAAUCUAGAACUCAAAGUCAGAGCUAUAGAUAUAAAAUGGAAAAAUCACAGCAUAUAGAUAGAGAUUAAAGUCUAGGAACUGAGUAAAGUCACCUAUAGAGAAAAGAUAGAGAAGUGAAGAGGAGAGAGAUCAAGUCCUAUAGCACUUUUAAUAAGAUCAGGCAAUCUCCUUACCAAAAAAAAAUGUGGUCUCUCAGAAGAAGAAAUGAGAGACUGGGGGAAAAAAAUAAAGAAUUAGGUCAAGGGACAAAUGCUGCUCUGAAUACAAUAAGAAAAGGACAGGAACUGGCCUCAGGAUUUGUCAAAAUGAAAAUUGUUGAGAACUUAGACAAGACCAGAUUCAACAGAUCAGUGGAGAUGAAAACCUAAUAGGUUUAAAAAAAAAAAAAAACUGAGGGAGGGAAAAGAGUGGAUAUAGAUUUCACUUUCAAGGGGCUUUGCUGUAAAGGGGAACAGAAAAAAGGCAGUUGACAGAAAGUUGAGGACAAGGGGCUAAAAAAUACUGGUUUCAAGUUUGGAGUCAUUAUAGCACUUUUUUUAUGUUAAUGGGUAUAAUUCAUGAAAAAGGAUAAAACUGAAGACACGGGACAGUGAAAUCAUAAUUCCAGAAUCUAAAUCUGUGUGUUGGCAAGAUAGGUUGGAACUUGAAGUGGAGUGAUUAGUCUUAGAUAGGAGCAGGGAUAAUUCUAUUGUGAUCCUAGGGAAGGUGCAGCAUAUGGGCUCAUCAGGCUAUGGACUUGGUAUUGGGAAUGUGGAAUAAGAAGCCAGGCCAUCAGCUGUAGUCCCAGCUACUCGGGAGGCUGAGGCAGGAGAAUGGCGUGAACCCGGGAAGCGGAGCUUGCAGUGAGCCGAGAUUGCGCCACUGCAGUCCGCAGUCCGGCCUGGGCGACAGAGCGAGACUCCGUCUCAAAAAAAAAAAGAAGCCAGGCCAUCAGGUUAGAGAAUAUGAGAUAAAAAAUGGUUGUCAGGAGAAAGAGAAAGUUAAAGUACUAGGAAAAUAUAGUAAGAUUGGGCAGCAUUAAAUACCUGCUUGAAAUUUAUCAUCAUAAAUGUAAUGUGAAAUCUGUCUCCAGUUAUGUGUUUUUCUCUAGUAACAUUCAGGAGCUUGAAUAGUGGCACAAAGUAGCUGGAGAGUUGGGUGUAGCUUUAGAGAUUUUGACAAGAAAAUACAAUAGAGUAGCAAGGAGCAAAGGAAUUAUGUGUAUGAUUAAAGUGAUAGAGCCUAGAAUCUGAGCCAGAUAAAGAAGGACGUGAGCAUAUUGGGAGUGAGAGUGGUAUAGUAAAAAGUGGUAGGGUCAAUAAAUUGGAGGUCUGAAAGAGAUAUAAAAAUUUUAGACGAAGGGAGCUAGAAUAAGUAGGCUUUAAAAUUAGAAGAUGGUAGUUAGCAAAUCUGCACUUAAAAAUCAAAAUUUUAGAAGUAAUGUGGUUAUUGGUGAUGACAAGGCCAACCAGUGUUUCAAAAACUUUUUAAAAUGGACAUAGUAAGGCCAGGCGUGGUGGCUCACACCUGUAAUCCUGGCACUUUGGGAGGCCAAGGCAGGUGGAUCAAGAGGUCAGGGGAUCGAGACCAUCCUGGCUAACACGGUGAAACCCCAUCUCUACUAAAAAUACAAAAAAUUAGCCGGACAUGGUAGCGGGCGCCUAUAGUCCCAGCUACUUGGGAGGCUGAGGCAAGAGAAUGGCGUGAACCCAGGAGGCAGAGUUUGCAGUGAACAGAGAUCGCGCCACUGCACUCCAGCCUGCCUGGAGUGCUUUAUUUUUGAGAUAGAGCGAGACUCUAUCUCAAAAAUAAAAUAAAAUAAAAUAAAAUAGACAUAGUAAGUAAUAUGAUGUUCAAGGCAACUCAAUAUGCACAAUGCAUACAUAAUAUGUAAUUGAAAAAAUUAUGAAACAAUAUUUACCUGACUUCAUUCAAUAAAGUCCAAUAUUUUAAAA